GUGUGUAGCUGGGACGGUGCUGGUCUGAGCUGGACCUUGUCUGAUGGCUUCCUCCAACCCUCCUCCACAGCCUGCCAUAGGAGAUCAGCUGGUUCCAGGAGUCCCAGGCCCCUCCUCUGAGGCAGAGGACGACCCAGGAGAGGCGUUUGAGUUUGAUGACAGUGAUGAUGAAGAGGACACCAGCGCAGCCCUGGGCGUCCCCAGCCUUGCUCCUGAGAGGGACACAGACCCCCCACUGAUCCACUUGGACUCCAUCCCUGUCACUGACCCAGACCCAGCAGCUGCUCCACCCGGCACAGGGGUGCCAGCCUGGGUGAGCAAUGGGGAUGCAGCGGACGCAGCCUUCUCCGGGGCCCGGCACUCCAGCUGGAAGCGGAAGAGUUCCCGUCGCAUUGACCGGUUCACUUUCCCCGCCCUGGAAGAGGAUGUGAUUUAUGACGACGUCCCCUGCGAGAGCCCAGAUGCGCAUCAGCCCGCAGGGGCAGAGAGGAACCUGCUCUACGAGGAUGCGCACCGGGCUGGGGCCCCUCGGCAGGCGGAGGACCUAGGCUGGAGCUCCAGUGAGUUCGAGAGCUACAGCGAGGACUCGGGGGAGGAGGCCAAGCCGGAGGUCGAGGUCGAGCCCGCCAAGCACCGAGUGUCCUUCCAGCCCAAGAUGACCCAGCUCAUGAAGGCCGCCAAGAGCGGGACCAAGGAUGGGCUGGAGAAGACACGGAUGGCCGUGAUGCGCAAAGUCUCCUUCCUGCACAGGAAGGACGUCCUCGACUUUCCAGGUGACUCGGAGGAGGAGGACAUGGGGCUCCUGGAGGUCAGCGUUUCGGACAUCAAGCCCCCAGCCCCAGAGCUGGGCCCCAUGCCAGAGGGCCUGAGCCCUCAGCAGGUGGUCCGGAGGCAUAUCCUGGGCUCCAUCGUGCAGAGCGAAGGCAGCUACGUGGAGUCUCUGAAGCGGAUACUCCAGGACUACCGCAACCCCCUGAUGGAGAUGGAGCCCAAGGCGCUGAGCGCCCGCAAGUGCCAGGUGGUGUUCUUCCGCGUGAAGGAGAUCCUGCACUGCCACUCCAUGUUCCAGAUCGCCCUGUCCUCCCGCGUGGCUGAGUGGGAUUCCACCGAGAAGAUCGGGGACCUCUUCGUGGCCUCGUUUUCCAAGUCCAUGGUGCUAGAUGUGUACAGUGACUACGUGAACAACUUCACCAGUGCCAUGUCCAUCAUCAAGAAGGCCUGCCUCACCAAGCCUGCCUUCCUCGAGUUCCUCAAGCGACGGCAGGUGUGCAGCCCAGACCGUGUCACCCUCUACGGGCUGAUGGUCAAGCCCAUCCAGAGGUUCCCACAGUUCAUACUCCUGCUUCAGGACAUGCUGAAGAACACCCCCAGGGGCCAUCCGGACAGGCUGUCGCUGCAGCUGGCCCUCACAGAGCUGGAGACGCUGGCUGAGAAGCUGAACGAGCAGAAGCGGCUGGCUGACCAGGUGGCUGAGAUCCAGCAGCUGACCAAGAGCGUCAGUGACCGCAGCAGCCUCAACAAGCUGUUGACCUCAGGCCAGCGGCAGCUGCUCCUGUGUGAGACGUUGACGGAGACCGUGUACGGUGACCGCGGGCAGCUAAUUAAGUCCAAGGAGCGUCGGGUCUUCCUGCUCAACGACAUGCUUGUCUGUGCCAACAUCAACUUCAAGCCUGCCAACCACAGGGGCCAGCUGGAGAUCAGCAGCCUGGUGCCCCUGGGGCCCAAGUAUGUGGUGAAGUGGAACACGGCGCUGCCCCAGGUGCAGGUGGUGGAGGUGGGCCAGGACGGUGGCACCUAUGACAAGGACAAUGUGCUCAUCCAGCACUCAGGCGCCAAGAAGGCCUCUGCCUCAGGGCAGGCUCAGAAUAAGGUGUACCUCGGCCCCCCACGCCUCUUCCAGGAGCUGCAGGACCUGCAGAAGGACCUGGCCGUGGUGGAGCAGAUCACGCUUCUCAUCAGCACGCUGCACGGCACCUACCAGAACCUGAACAUGACUGUGGCUCAAGACUGGUGCCUGGCCCUGCAGAGGCUGAUGCGGGUGAAGGAGGAAGAGAUCCACUCGGCCAACAAGUGCCGUCUCAGGCUCCUGCUUCCUGGGAAACCCGACAAGUCCGGCCGCCCCAUUAGCUUCAUGGUGGUUUUCAUCACCCCCAACCCCCUGAGCAAGAUUUCCUGGGUCAACAGGUUACAUUUGGCCAAAAUCGGACUCCGGGAGGAGAACCAGCCAGGCUGGCUAUGCCCGGAUGAGGACAAGAAGAGCAAAGCCCCAUUCUGGUGCCCGAUCCUGGCCUGCUGCAUCCCUGCCUUCUCCUCCCGGGCACUCAGCCUGCAGCUUGGGGCCCUGGUCCACAGUCCUGUCAACUGUCCCCUGCUGGGUUUCUCAGCAGUCAGCACCUCCCUUCCACAGGGCUACCUCUGGGUCGGGGGCGGACAGGAAGGCGCAGGGGGCCAGGUGGAAAUCUUUUCCUUGAACCGGCCCUCGCCCCGCACCGUCAAGUCCUUCCCACUGGCAGCCCCUGUGCUCUGCAUGGAGUAUAUCCCGGAGCUGGAGGAGGAGGCGGAGAGCAGAGACGAGAGCCCGACAGUUGCUGACCCCUCGGCCACGGUGCAUCCAACCAUCUGCCUCGGGCUCCAGGAUGGCAGCAUCCUCCUCUACAGCAGUGUGGACACUGGCACCCAGUGCCUGGUGAGCUGCAGGAGCCCAGGUCUGCAGCCUGUGCUCUGCCUGCGACACAGCCCCUUCCACCUGCUCGCUGGCCUGCAGGAUGGGACCCUUGCUGCUUACCCUCGGACCAGCGGAGGUGUCCUGUGGGACCUGGAGAGCCCUCCCGUGUGCCUGACUGUGGGGCCCGGGCCUGUCCGCACCCUGUUGAGCCUGGAGGAUGCCGUGUGGGCCAGCUGUGGGCCCCGGGUCACUGUCCUGGAAGCCACCACCCUGCAGCCUCAGCAAAGCUUCGAGGCGCACCAGGACGAGGCAGUGAGCGUGACACACAUGGUGAAGGCGGGCAGCGGCGUCUGGAUGGCCUUCUCCUCCGGCACCUCCAUCCGCCUCUUCCACACUGAGACCCUGGAGCAUCUGCAAGAGAUCAACAUCGCCACCAGGACCACCUUCCUCCUGCCAGACAGGUCAUUAAUAAAAUGUUCUCCAAGAGCCUGAGCUUUUUAAAGUUGUAUAUCUCCAGAUAGAUGGCUUGGGUGAGUUGAACACUGCCGCAUUAAGUCUCUGUGAUAAAAUAUUUAUUCACCAUUAGAAUUUUUUUUUUCUUUCGGACUGUUUGUGAAGUGUCUUGCUCUUUUCCUUGAGGUGGAGGGGGAGGGGGAAGGCCCCAGAAUGAGGUCUGCAGAUGAAGCCAUUUCUCAAUUCCGGCAUCUCUUUCGGUUUCUUGCUUGCCUUCCUCCCAUUUGUCGGUUUUGCCGUCCAGUGGGGGCUGGGAGGAUGCAGGGGCAGCAGGAAAUGGUCUCCUGCCGGUCUCCAUGCCCUGGGGGUCUUGGAGAGGGAGGCGAUGAGGCUUGUGGAAUGAAAAAUUCACCACUGUCCCCUCUCUUGGCUUAAUUGUUCUUGUGGGUUUAUGGCUCUGAUGGAGCUGAUCUUAAGACAUUAGCGUCCAGAUCCUUUUAAUAAUCAUAAACAUUAUCCUAAUAGCCUCUAUUUAUUGAUUGUAUACUAUGGGCUAAGAGCUGUGCUCAAUUGUGUAUAUAUAUUAUAUGUAUAUAUAUAUGUGUGUAUAUAUUUAAUAUUUCUAAUAAUUAUAAAAUUGAGCAAGGCAGGUUUGUAGUACUCAUUGAUGGAUGAGAGAAAUGAUUUGUCCAAGUUUUCUCCUUUCCUUCAUCCAUCCAUCUGUCCAUCCAUCCAUCCAUUUACUCAUUCACUCACAGAUACUUCUUGAGAGUCUACCAUGAGCCAAGGUACUUGGCCAGGAGUUGGGGAGUUAACCAUGAGCACACAGAUAAGUCACUGCCCUCACAAAGCUUGUCAUAAGUAAACAAAUAGCAAAAUAAGGUCAUCACAGACCUUGACCAGGGCUAAGAAGAGAAGUCAGCUGUUGAAAGGGGCUCAUGGCCUGAGCCUCCCAUGUUGGCCAACUCCAGGAGGGCUGGGGGCCUGACCCUGGACCGGAGGCUGCCAUCAUAGUUCUGAGCCUUCACUUUUGGAAUGGAUUUAGGUGUGGGAAAUAGUCCCAGCUCCACAGACACCCAGGUACUGUUUGUGAAAUAGCCCCUGUUGGCCAAGGCUGUAAGUCACUAGUGGGCUUUUUUUUUCAGCCUAGUUUGCAUUUCCACAUUGCAGGGACGCUAUGAAUGUGAUUUUUUGAGUUUGCAUCAUGUUGCCAGACUCGAAUCCCACCGCCUGCUUGAUAGCUCCAUUCGGGUGUGUCUAAUUUGUGUCUCAGACCACACAUCCAACCAGGAGCUCUGGGCUUCAACCCCCAAACCGGCUCCUUUGCCAUCCCAGGCCAUGGCACUGCUAUGCACCCAGCUGCUCCAGGCAGAGGAGCCUCAGUGCUAUCCUGGGUUCCUUCCUCUGCUCCACCUCUGCUCCCCUCUCCCAGCAGCUCUGUCGCUCUGCUCCAAACAGGUCUAAAACAGGUUGGGCUCUCCUCACCUCACUGCCGCCGCCCUUCCCACCUGGGCAGCUGCGGGAGCCCCUGCUGGGCUCCUUGCUCCUCCCACUCCCACCCUCCACAACUGUAGCUAGAACGUUCCACUCAAAUCACGUCACGCUACUCCCCUGCCUAGGCCUUCCGGUAGCUUUUCACUGCAGCCAGAAUUAUGAGCCCCAGUCCUGGCCCUGACCCAUCCCCUCUUCUGACCAUCUGGAGUCUGCCUUCUGUGCCCCAGGUGCACUGGCUUCACUCUGCUCGGCGGACUGGAUGAGCUCAUUCCUGUCACAGGGCCUUUGCAUGCCCUGUCUCCUGGGCCUUGGCUCAGGUCUUGGUGUGGCCACCUCCGCCUUGUCACCCAGCAGCCUCACGCCUGCCUCCCUAUCCUUCCAGGAAGUAGAGGGAGGCCUGAAGACCCGGGAAUCCUCCACUGGCUCUGCCCUGUCGCCCUGUUUCAAUCCUCUGCCUGGUGUUUACAUCCCUUGUUUCUGUUUUUGUUUCCUGUAUCUCCUCUCUACACCUCUGUGUCUAAUACAGUAGCCAUUAUUACAAUGAAAGAAAAUAACACAUUCAGUCCCUCAGUGCCACUAGCUAUAUUUCCAGUGCUCGGAAGCCACAUGUGGCUGAUGGCUGUCAAAUUGGACAGCACGGUAGGGAACAUGUCCAUCAUCAAAGAAAGUUCUAGAGUGUCUGCUCCUUAAGACAGGACUCUAUGUACAUGGUCCCAGCUGUGCCCCCAGCACCUAGUGUGGGGUCUGCCAUGCAGUAGGCAUCUGGGAGGUAAAUGGAUUGGUGAUGGGAUGGCACACUGUGUUAGGCAAUGCUGGGUGUACCCCGAGUCGGUAACCUGCCUUUUGGGGUGAGAGAGCCACACCAUUUCUCUCUGUGCCUGCACUGCAGAGGAAGCACAUACACCCACAUGUAUGGAGUUGAAGUGUCAUGCCCAAGGAGGGAGAGGUGAUGGAAGCACUGGGCAGUGGUGAGCAGCAGACCUCAACUCCACCCCACCCUGCACUCACCAGGUGGGGGACCUCUUUGAGCCUUAACAUCCGUGCCUGGAAAAUGGGGCCGGCAUUUGUGUCUUGCAUACGUCUUGGCUGUUGCAAGCCUUGUGUCAGAUGAGAGCAGGUAUACGAGUGCUUUGGAAACUCCAAAGCUGUGUUUUUUCAAAUGUGAUCCAUGGACCAGAAGCAGCAGAAAGUGGAAACCUUCUGGAAUGCAGCCUAAGCCUCUCCCAGAGGGCAGCAGGAUCAGGGCAAGAAGGAGACAGCCCUUUAGAAAGGCAGCUGCCCAGUGAAGCCUAAGGAAGUGUGGCAGCGCCGUCCACCCUGUGUGUGACAUGGUGGAGGGUCUGUCCCUGAGCCGGCAGCCUGUACCCCACGCCUCUCAGCCCCCUCAGAAAGCCUCCUGCCCCCUGCACUCCCAGCCUCUCCCUUGUGCCCAUUCCCAUUGCUAGAAUUGUUGGCAACAGUGCAGCAGCAGCGAUGACAGCAGGUAGCGCCCAUUUUGCCAUGUGCAGGCACGGGGUUGUUUUACGUUCAUUCAUUUAACCCAAUGGAGAGUAUCUGUGUUCCAAACAUCAAAAAGGGACAGUAAAAAUACGGUCCUAUAGGACUGCCAUUGUAUACAUGGUCUGUUGUUGACUGAAAGGUCAUUAUGUGACAUGUGACUGUAUUAUCCUUGGCCCCUUUUACAAGUGAGGACACCAUGGCCCAGAGGAGUUUAGGAUGGGCCCCAGGUCAUGUAGCUGGAGAGUGGCAGAGCCAAGGUGUGAAUCCCGCACCUGGCUCUGGAGCCCUGUUCUCAGCCACCGUGCUGGGCAGCCCACACCUGGCAUCCUCUCUGUUAGGAGCAGGGGCCUGCCCCCACGCCCUCUCUGACAUUGCUAUUCUUGCUAAAAUGAAGAGACAGAGCUGAGGGGAGAGCUAAAAAGAAUGAAUCUGGACUGGCAUCAGAAACAUGCUGCUUCCCACCAGCGAGUUUUGUGCUUCACUCUUG